CUCAGCUGUCCGGGCUGCUUUCGCCUCCGCCUGUGGAUGCUGCGCCUCUCCGAACGCAACAUGAAGGUGCUCCUUGCCGCCGCCCUCAUCGCGGGGUCCGUCUUCUUCCUGCUGCUGCCGGGACCUUCUGCGGCCGAUGAGAAGAAGAAGGGGCCCAAAGUCACCGUCAAGGUGUAUUUUGACCUACGAAUUGGAGAUGAAGAUGUAGGCCGGGUGAUCUUUGGUCUCUUCGGAAAGACUGUUCCAAAAACAGUGGAUAAUUUUGUGGCCUUAGCUACAGGAGAGAAAGGAUUUGGCUACAAAAACAGCAAAUUCCAUCGUGUAAUCAAGGACUUCAUGAUCCAGGGCGGAGACUUCACCAGGGGAGAUGGCACAGGAGGAAAGAGCAUCUACGGUGAGCGCUUCCCCGAUGAGAACUUCAAACUGAAGCACUACGGGCCUGGCUGGGUGAGCAUGGCCAACGCAGGCAAAGACACCAACGGCUCCCAGUUCUUCAUCACGACAGUCAAGACAGCCUGGCUAGAUGGCAAGCAUGUGGUGUUUGGCAAAGUUCUAGAGGGCAUGGAGGUGGUGCGGAAGGUGGAGAGCACCAAGACAGACAGCCGGGAUAAACCCCUGAAGGAUGUGAUCAUCGCAGACUGCGGCAAGAUCGAGGUGGAGAAGCCCUUUGCCAUCGCCAAGGAGUAGGGCACAGGGACAUCUUUCUUUGAGUGACCGUCUGUGCAGGCCCUGUAGUCCGCCACAGGGCUCUGAGCUGCACUGGCCCCGGUGCUGGCAUCUGGUGGAGCGGACCCACUCCCCUCACAUUCCACAGGCCCAUGGACUCACUUUUGUAACAAACUCCUACCAACACUGACCAAUAAAAAAAAAUGUGGGUUUUUUUUUUUUUAAUA